UGCCGAGGCUGGUCUCGAACUCAUGGCUUCAAGAGAUCUUCCCGCCUUGGCCUCCUACAGUGCUGGGAUUACAGCCAGGAACUGCUGUGCCCAGCUAGCUCUUUUUAAUCCACUUUGUCAACCUCUGCCUUUUAAUUAGAAUUUGUAAACAUUAACUUUUUUUUUUUUUUUUUUUGAGAUGGAGUCUCGCUCUGUCUUCCAGGCUGGAGUGCAAUGAUGCAAUCUCGGCUCACUGCAACCUCCGCCUCCCCGUUCAAGCAAUUCUCCUGCCUCAGCCUCCUGAGUAGCUGGGAUUACAGGCACACGCCACCAUGCCCAGCUAAUUUUUGUAUUUUUAGUAGAGACGGGGUUUCACCACGUUGGUCAGGCUGGUCUCAAACUCCUGACCUCGUGGUCCGCCCGCUUCAGCCUCCCAAAGUGCUGGGAUUACAGGCAUGAGCCACCGCGCCCAGCCAACAUUAACAUUUAAUGAAAUUAUUUAUAUGGUUAGAUUUAGGUGCACUUUUAUUAUUUGUUUCCUAUUUGUCCCCUCUGUUUUUUGUUUGUUUGUUCUUUUUCUUUGGAAUUGUUGGGCUAGUUCUGAGCAUUUCAUUUAUCUGUUGGCUUUUCGGAUCUGUGUCUUUGUGUUGUGUCUUAGUCAUUGCUCUGGAGGUUCCAGUCUGCACACCUGUUAGCCUUCACUGUCUGCUCAGAGUUCAUACUGUGCCCCUCACAGAAACGUGGGGACCUUGCAGUCAUCUGGGUCCCUCGAAUCCCCUCCUGACCUUUCUGUUGCCUUUCAUGUGGAUUACUUCUGUGCGCGUUGGAAGCCAACUACGCAGUAUUUUUUUGUCUACAGUCUUACAUAUUUAAGAACUCCUAAGAGGAAAACAAUAGUAUUUUAUAUUUACCAAUUCUGUUGCUCUCCCUUCCCUCCUCAAGAUCCAGGCUUCCCUCUGGUAUCAUUUUCCUUCAACCCGAGGAACUUUCUUGAGCAUUCCUUAUACAGCAGCUGUAUUAGUGACAAACUAUGUUCGUUUUCUGCCAUCUAGAAUCUUUAUUGCACCUUCGUUUCUGAAAGAUAUUUUCCCUGCGUAUAGAAUACCUCGGUGCCUCUUUUCUGACAACACUUAAAAAUAUCCCUACAUAAUGGUUAAAAGCAGGGUGGAUCCUGGCCUAGAUCCUGGACCAGAAGAAGGACGCUCUUGGGAAACUGCUGAGCCCCAAGCCCCACCUGGAGCUCAGUUAGUAGCGGUGCAGCGGCGGCGGCCGCACAGGCACGGCUGCGGGGGCACUGGGGAGGAAGUCCGCAGGGAUGCCUUUGCACCUUGUCCACAAAUCUAAAACCAUCUCAAAAUCAGCUGUCCUGUAAAAUAUAUUUACAGGAAGGGUAUCAAGGGGAGGGUGUCCCAUGGAGAGGUGGCCCGGCACGGGAACUCAGCCAGUCGGAGAACAGAGACCCGCUAAAGAAUGGGGAGCUCUGGGAGCAGGCGGGGAGGUGGAGCUGAGGGCGGGUCACAGCAGGUAGGGGUUGAGCAGCUCCAUAAAUAUCUUAAAGUGCAUGGAGGCCCGGUUUCUUAUAGGCGGAGAAUGGAGUUACCAAGACCACAAGAGAAAAUUAGAAUGACCCCAGAGUGCUGAAUUGGGAAUGAGGACGUCCUGUGCACAGCUGGCCUGCUGCCUCCCACGUGUCAGGGCUGGCUCGGGAGUCAGGAGAGGCUGAGGAACCUUCCAGCCCAAGGAGCUGGACAAGGUGUGGCAGCUGCAGGCAGCCGGGAUAGGGACGCAGACUUUCCUACAGGGAGAGGCACUGCUGAGACCGGGGCCCACGUGGGAGGGGCUGUCGGUCAUGGCCAGUCUCAAUGACACCCUGGUUCUGGAGGGGACACCAUUUUCUCUAGGAAACACACAUGGACUGUUCUGGGUGCAGGGAAGUCCAGUCGGCGACUGACUCUUAAGUGAUUCAGGAGGAAGUUCUUUGUACUCUUCUUCCAGCUUUUCUGUAACUGUGAUUGCCUCAGAAUUAAAGCAGAAUGGCCAAGGACCCCACAGAGAUAGUGACCCCCCCAAAGGAGGUGGCACCUUUUCAGAGGAGUGAGGCUGGGGAGAGGGAGGCGUCCGAGGCACUGCGAGGGAGGAGGCAGGCGGUGUCCCCUCGUUGUGCUCCCGCUCUGGCCCCGUGUUGAGUUUUCAGCCGUCCACUGGGGCCCCUUCUGUACACAUCUUUUGUAGUCAGGAUGGGGAGCACCUUGUAAGGUCCCUCCUGUGCGACCUGCUGAAGACUGGGGAGCUCUGGGAGCAGGCAGGUAUUUGUGCUCAUGGUGAAGGGAGAGGGGCUGUCCUCUCCUGGAGGGCAGGGUCAGGACUUCCUCACUGUGCCCUUGGCACCUGCAAGGUAGCCGGCUGUCAUGAGCGGCUUGUUGAAUGAGUGACAGCUUAAAUGAGGCUUUGAGAGUGACAGUAGCUGGCACUUAGAGUCUGCAGCUGUGCCAACCCUGUCGCUCCGGGGAUAUUUCCACCCACACUACACAUCAGGCACCAAAUGUGUGGGUUUUCCACACCAACAAUUCGCCAGUCCUCUGCAGACACCAGCCAGGCAUCCUGUAAUUCAGUUCAGUCUGACCCUGCCGCGGUUAUCAGGGACCCCAGCGUUAGGGGCUCAGUCACCCCCCACUUCAGAUGCUAAUUGCAAGUAGUGGGUCCCUGGGGUACCCACACUUCUGUCCAUCUUGGCUACACAUUGGGAGUUCCUACGACCCCUUCAGGUUUGAUGAUUUGCGGUAGUGGCUCACAGAACUCAGGAAGGCACUUGGUUUGCAUUGCCAGUUUACUAUAAAGGAUGCCACAGCGGGCACAGGCAGGCAGCUGGGUGAGGAGGGGCACGGGCGAGGCCCAGAGGGUCCUAAGCAUAGGAGCCUUUGUCCCCAGGGAGUUGUGUGGCUGGCCUUACAGCACGGGGAUGAGUUCACCAAACUGAAAGCUUUCCAGAGCCCCUAGUUCCAGGAUUUCCAUGGAGGCCUCAUCAUGGAGACAUGAUCAGUUAUGAACUCAGCCUCCAGCCCCUCUGCCCUUUUUGGAGGGUGGGGGUGGGGCCGAAAGGUCCAGGCUUCUCAUCGUGGCUUGGUCUUUAUGAUGACCAGCCCCCUCCCAAGGCCAUCCAGGAGCCCACCAAGAGGUGCCUCAUUAGAACAGAAGACUCUCCUGUCACCUGGGAAGUCCAAGGGAUUUAGGAGCUCUGUGUCAGGCACCCCUAUCGCCCCUGUCACUCAGGAAAUUACCAGCGUUCUGAGAGCUCUGUGUCAGGAGCCAGGAGCAGGGGCCAAGUGUGUUCUUCUCAUUCUAUCGGUGCCACAGCCAGGGCCGCGGUUGUGCAGCCGUGUGGAUCAGCUCAGCCCGUCCUCACCCAGCCGUGUGAGGAGGCCGAGGCCACACAGGUGGAUGGCCUUCCCUUAGAGUUACUUUCCAGAGCCUGGGUGCUUAGCCGCUAUGCCCCAUGUUUAAUAUUCUUGUGUUCCAAUGUAACAACUUUAAAAUUACACAGGAUAACACUCUUGAUAACAUUUUAAUAAAUGGGUGUUUUUCUUUUCAAGAAAUUUUGACUUGCACUUCAGAUUUCCUUUUUAAUAUUUUCGUUGAGCGGAACCUUGCUAUUCCAUAAGAGGAUGUGUCCAGUGUUGUGGAAGAUUUCAUGUUUUAAAUCCUUUGUACAGAAAUCCUGCUCCCAAGUCACAGAUAGGCUGACGGGUCAGAGGGCAAGACGUGACCCAGGGCCGAGAGGGUGAGUGACCAGGAAAAUCGGAUUCAUCAGUUCACUUGUUUGUUUCAGAAACGUGCACAAAGACCUGCUGCAUGAGGCCCUCGUCUUCAGUUUCUGUUUCAUGCCCAGCAUUAAACCAAGUAUCUCAUUUUGCCAAUUUGACUUCUGUAGGGGCCAUGGCACCUGCAAGGUGUUUCUCAGCAAGAUUGAGGACCGUGUUUCAGGGCGUGGGGCAUUGGGCUUUGUCCACAUGGGCUGGCCUGAAGCCCAGCCGGCUACUGCCACAGCGGGCUUCUCCCAGGCUGCUCUCGGUCGGCCGUGCGGACCUCGCCAAGCAUCAGGAACUCCCGGGGAAGAAGCUGCUCUCUGAGAAAAAGCUGAAAAGGUACUUUGUGGACUAUCGGAGAGUGCUUGUCUGUGGAGGAAACGGAGGCGCUGGGGCAAGCUGCUUCCACAGUGAGCCCCGCAAGGAGUUUGGAGGCCCUGAUGGAGGGGACGGAGGCAACGGUGGACACGUCAUUCUGAGAGUUGACCAGCAAGUCAAGUCCCUGUCGUCGGUCCUGUCGCGGUACCAGGGUUUCAGUGGAGAAGAUGGAGGGAGUAAAAACUGCUUCGGGCGCAGUGGCGCCGUCCUCUACAUCCGGGUCCCCGUGGGCACGCUGGUGAAGGAGGGAGGCAGAGUUGUGGCCGACCUGUCUUGCGUGGGAGAUGAGUACAUUGCCGCGCUGGGCGGGGCAGGAGGGAAAGGCAACCGCUUCUUCCUGGCCAACAACAACCGUGCCCCUGUGACCUGUACCCCUGGACAGCCAGGACAGCAGCGAGUUCUCCACCUGGAGCUCAAGACGGUGGCCCACGCCGGAAUGGUGGGAUUCCCCAACGCCGGGAAGUCCUCACUGCUCCGGGCCAUUUCAAACGCCAGACCCGCCGUGGCUUCCUACCCGUUCACCACCCUGAAGCCCCACGUCGGGAUCGUCCACUACGAAGGCCACCUACAAAUAGCAGUGGCCGACAUCCCCGGCAUCAUACGAGGCGCCCACCAGAACAGGGGUCUGGGGUCCGCCUUCCUCAGGCACAUCGAGCGCUGCCGCUUUCUCUUGUUCGUGGUGGAUCUUUCUCAGCCUGAGCCGUGGACUCAAGUUGACGAUUUAAAAUAUGAACUGGAGAUGUAUGAAAAGGGCCUGUCUGCGAGGCCCCACGCAAUCGUCGCAAACAAGAUUGACCUCCCUGAAGCCCAAGCCAAUCUGUCCCAGCUCCGGGAUCACUUGGGACAGGAGGUCAUCGUGCUGUCGGCGUUGACCGGCGAGAACCUGGAGCAGCUGCUGUUGCACCUGAAGGUGCUGUAUGACGCCUACGCGGAGGCCGAGCUGGGCCAGGGCCGCCAGCCGCUCAGGUGGUAGCCACGCCAGAGCGGGGUCGCCUCUGGGCCUCUGUCUGAGCAAACCUGGGUGUGAAUUCGGUGGUUUUGAAUGCAUAAAGUGCCUUGUGGACACGGGGGAGUUGUGGUGCUUCUGGGUCUCUGGGCCCCGCCUGCUGGCCUGAGAUGCCCUCAUGUUGGGAAGCAUUCCGUGCCCCCUACCCCGCCUGCCCUCCGUAUUUCCUGCACCUGUCAGCCUGCACCGACUGAUGAGCCAGUUGCUCAUUUGUGCUGAUUAACACCCCUAAUAAGGGGUUGGGGUGCCCAUAACGGGGUGGCCCUGCCGCUGACUCAGGUCUCCGCCAUGCACGCGUGGACUCUCGGAUGAGCUCAGCAGAACCGCACAGCCAGAGCCCCAGGUCAGAAGUGCAGACCAGGGUUCUCAGCACAGUGCCCGUCGUGCUUCCAUGGCUUGCUACGGAGAGAGACCUCUGGAUCCACACUGGGGCUGCGUCUGGCCCGUUGUCCAGCAGCCCUGCGGUACCGCAAGCCCAGGCACCAGUGUCUCGGGGGGCCUCACUGCUGCGCAAGGGGUGGGGCCGAGGAUGCAAGUCCAGGCAGAGCGGCGCAGGCAGCUGUGAGCUUUUCUCCAUCAGCCGUCUGAGAAGAGCAGUGAGGCCAGCUGCUUCCUGUCCUUCAGAACACUUCUCUGUGCUCAGUGGGAGCCAGGAAGCCUCAGGCUUCACGACUGAAUGCACCCAAUAUCCGACCUGGCUGCGUGUUUCUGGCUGGGCUGCCGUGUGCACAGCAAGUUAACUAGAGGGGCUGUGGGCCAUGGAACUGUCAGCGUUAUUCUCAGAAGGCGGCCGUGGCAUGGGCAGGGUAUAGUGAGGAGUGGAAGGAGACGUGUGCCUGGUAAUAUGGGGCGGAAUUUCCACUCAGCUCCAUUUGCUGGGGAUUUAAAGAGAACCCUUGUGCUACGCCAGGCAGUUACCGAGCCGAAGGGAGAUGAUGGGCCUUCGCCCCUCAGUGGGAUGGCAGCUGAGGGGGCCCUGCAUUUGACCGUCGAGACUGCAGCAGCGCCUUUCCUGUCUGUGGUUUAAGUCUUUGCAGUCAAGUACUGAUGCAUCCAAGCCAGGCCCAUGCCUGGUGUCUCCCUGACUGCAGAGGAGCCCCAGGGCAAGGACAGCUCAGCUGCUGGCAGCCUGCCUGGCCCAUAGACAUCCCCCAAGUAGUCUCAGGCCUCUGACAUGUCCCUGAGGGGCCCCUAAGAAAGAAAGUGGAGGGGACACUCCAGAGGCUGUCGUGGGAGGAUCAUGUGAGCCUGGGAGGUCAAGGCUGCAGUGAGCCGUGAUUGCACCACUGCACUCCAGCCUGAGUGACAGAGCGAGACCCUGUCUCAAAAAACAAACAAACAAACAAACAAAAACAGAACAUUCUGGGCACGGUGGCUCAUGCCUGUAGUCCCAGCACUUUGGGAGGCCGAGGCUGGUGGAUCACAAGGUCAGGAGAUUGAGACCAUCCUGGCUAACACAGUGAAACCCCGUCUCUACUAAAAAUACAAAAAAAUUAGCCAGGCGUGGUGGCGGUCACCUGUAGUCCCAGCUACUCGGGAGGCUGAAGCAGGAGAAUGGCGUGAACCUGGGAGGCGGAGCUUGCAGUGAGCCGAGAUCACACCACUGCACUCCAGCCUGAGCGACAGAGCAAGACUCCAUCUCAAAAAAAAAAAAAAAGUGGAGGGGACAAAGAAGCAGAGAAGGAUGAUCAGAAGGGGACCCCCAGCCCUUGGAGGAGAGACGGCAGCCUCAGGCCGCCACAAAGGAUUUUGUGGAGUCGCCCCAGGCCUGACGGCGUUAAUUAUCCCUGGCUUUCAUCUUGAUGCUCUUGCAGGGGAGGCUCAAGAUGCCUUGUGGCUCGACCCCUGCACGGAGCCCCCAGCCCAGCCUCCCCGUGGGUUGAAACCUUGAUCUGGGCCUGACUGUGGCUGCUCUGGGGACAUGCCCUCGUCCUUUGCUGAAGCUGAGGCUCCAGAGGGGGAGUCACUGCCACGAAGGUUGCCCAGAACUUUCCUUGCUGCAAAAAGCCCCAAGACUUCUCCCUGCCACACACACAGCUUUUGCCAUCGCGUUCUAAAAGCUGACAGCUUUCUCUCCAACACUGUUCUCCCUGAGUAGGGUAAAGCUACACUUGGCUUCCCCAGUUUCCUGUUUCCUGCCUAGAAACAAAUUUUUGUCAGUCUGCUUUUCAAAUGGGAUAUAUGAUUCACAUACCAUAAAAUUCACCACUUUAUAUAA